AACUCUGGUCCCGGGCAGCCAAGACAAAGCGAAAGGCAAGGCAGCAUGAGCCGAUCACCCCUCAAUCCCAGCCAACUCCGAUCAGUGGGCUCCCAGGAUGCCCUGGCCCCCUUGCCUCCACCUGCUCCCCAGAAUCCCUCCACCCACUCUUGGGACCCUUUGUGUGGAUCUCUGCCUUGGGGCCUCAGCUGUCUUCUGGCUCUGCAGCAUGUCUUGGUCAUGGCUUCUCUGCUCUGUGUCUCCCACCUGCUCCUGCUUUGCAGUCUCUCCCCAGGAGGACUCUCUUACUCCCCUUCUCAGCUCCUGGCCUCCAGCUUCUUUUCAUGUGGUAUGUCUACCAUCCUGCAAACUUGGAUGGGCAGCAGGCUGCCUCUUGUCCAGGCUCCAUCCUUAGAGUUCCUUAUCCCUGCUCUGGUGCUGACCAGCCAGAAGCUACCCCGGGCCAUCCAGACACCUGGAAACUGUGAGCACAGAGCAAGGGCAAGGGCCUCCCUCAUGCUGCACCUUUGUAGGGGACCUAGCUGCCAUGGCCUGGGGCACUGGAACACUUCUCUCCAGGAGGUGUCCGGGGCAGUGGUAGUAUCUGGGCUGCUGCAGGGCAUGAUGGGGCUGCUGGGGAGUCCCGGCCACGUGUUCCCCCACUGUGGGCCCCUGGUGCUGGCUCCCAGCCUGGUUGUGGCAGGGCUCUCUGCCCACAGGGAGGUAGCCCAGUUCUGCUUCACACACUGGGGGUUGGCCUUGCUGGUUAUCCUGCUCAUGGUGGUCUGUUCUCAGCACCUGGGCUCCUGCCAGUUUCAUGUGUGCCCCUGGAGGCGAGCUUCAACGUCAUCAACUCACACUCCUCUCCCUGUCUUCCGGCUCCUUUCGGUGCUGAUCCCAGUGGCCUGUGUGUGGAUUGUUUCUGCCUUUGUGGGAUUCAGUGUUAUCCCCCAGGAACUGUCUGCCCCCACCAAGGCACCAUGGAUUUGGCUGCCUCACCCAGGUGAGUGGAAUUGGCCUUUGCUGACGCCCAGAGCUCUGGCUGCAGGCAUCUCCAUGGCCUUGGCAGCCUCCACCAGUUCCCUGGGCUGCUAUGCCCUGUGUGGCCGGCUGCUGCAUUUGCCUCCCCCACCUCCACAUGCCUGCAGUCGAGGGCUGAGCCUGGAGGGGCUGGGCAGUGUGCUGGCCGGGCUGCUGGGAAGCCCCAUGGGCACUGCAUCCAGCUUCCCCAACGUGGGCAAAGUGGGUCUUAUCCAGGCUGGAUCUCAGCAAGUGGCUCACUUAGUGGGGCUACUCUGCGUGGGGCUUGGACUCUCCCCCAGGUUGGCUCAGCUCCUCACCACCAUCCCACUGCCUGUUGUUGGUGGGGUGCUGGGGGUGACCCAGGCUGUGGUUUUGUCUGCUGGAUUCUCCAGCUUCUACCUGGCUGACAUAGACUCUGGGCGAAAUAUCUUCAUUGUGGGCUUCUCCAUCUUCAUGGCCUUGCUGCUGCCAAGAUGGUUUCGGGAAGCCCCAGUCCUGUUCAGCACAGGCUGGAGCCCCUUGGAUGUAUUACUGCACUCACUGCUGACACAGCCCAUCUUCCUGGCUGGACUCUCAGGCUUCCUACUAGAGAACACGAUUCCUGGCACACAGCUUGAGCGAGGCCUAGGUCAAGGGCUACCAUCUCCUUUCACUGCCCAAGAGGCUCGAAUGCCUCAGAAGCCCAGGGAGAAGGCUGCUCAAGUGUACAGACUUCCUUUCCCCAUCCAAAACCUCUGUCCCUGCAUCCCCCAGCCUCUCCACUGCCUCUGCCCACUGCCUGAAGACCCUGGGGAUGAGGAAGGAGGCUCCUCUGAGCCAGAAGAGAUGGCAGACUUGCUGCCUGGCUCAGGGGAGCCAUGCCCUGAAUCUAGCAGAGAAGGGUUUAGGUCCCAGAAAUGACCAGAACGCCUACUUCUGCCCUGGUUAAUUUAGCCCUAACUCUCAUCUGCUGGAGAGUCAGCUCCCAAACUGUUCUUUCUUGUAGGCAGAGGAUAUGUGUGUGUGUAUUACAUGGGACUGUCUAGAGGUUCCAUUUCCCAAUAGGGUGGGUUGCCUUUCCUUGUCUUAAUUAGGCCUAACUGUUCCAGAGCAGAGGCCAUGAUUUAGUGGACCAUGAAUGAUUGAGAUUUUGCCUGUGUACUAUCAAUGCCACUUGAACCCCAGCAUUCACUUUAAUACUUACUGAGCAUCUCCCAUGUGCAAGGUCCUGGAACUACAGGGAUAAGACAGGGUCCAUGCCGUCUCAAGGCAUUUACGGUUUAAAAAGACCUUUGUAAUUACUAACGAAAAUGCAAAGCAGAAAGCAGUCUGUAAUAAAGAUUAAAAUAAUGCCGUGGGAGCAAA